AGAAACCAGGCGGCGCGUUCCCGGUGGCGGCGCCCUGGACUCCCGGGCCCGCGCAUCCCCGCCAGCCUUCCUUAAGGCGGAUGGGUGGCCCCCGAGACCCCGUCGGACCCAUGGUUUCCAGUGCAGCGCGGAGUGGGCGAUGCCAGCGUGCCAGGAGCCAUGUCUGACCAGGACGUUUGGAAGAUCAUAUCCAUGCCAGAGGCUCUUGUGAGGAGAUGAGUUGGUAAAGAGAGAGGCUGGGAUGAAGAUGCUGCCAGGAGUGGGCGUGUUUGGGACUGGCAGCUCCGCCCGAGUUCUGGUCCCACUGCUGAGGGCAGAAGGGUUCACUGUUGAGGCCCUGUGGGGGAAGACUGAGGAGGAGGCGAAGCAGCUUGCUGAGGAGAUGAACAUCGCCUUCUACACCAGCCGGACUGAUGACAUCUUGCUGCAUCAAGAUGUGGAUCUGGUGUGCAUCAGCAUCCCCCCUCCACUCACCCGGCAGAUAUCCGUGAAGGCUCUAGGUACGCCCGGCAGGCCACAGCAGGGGCAGAUCAUGUCUCUCCCUCUGGGCAGUCCUCUGAGGGUCACUCCUCUCCUCUGAGCUCUCCUUCCUGGGCUCGCAUCUGCAGGGAGGAGAACUCUGGGACAUCACUUGUCCCUGAAGCAGUGCUUGGGGAGGGCAUGAAAAAAGACAUAGCCUAACCUACCUCCCAUCUGUAAAUCCCUGAACAGAAAUUAAGGAAAUACUCUAAGAGACAGCCAUCAAGGGGCUGGAGAUGGUUGCAUCUCAGUCAACAUAAAGUUUGCCUCUGUGAAGUUAGAGGUCAGAGCCCUGGGUGGCGGGGAAUUGGUUGUGACUAGUGUGUUUGUUCUCCCAUUUCUGGGGCACACAGCACCACAGGAAGGAGAGGCUGUGUAGCAAGGCUACCAUUUCCCAUGUUUUGUCAGCGUUUGACUAUAGUGAGCACACACCCUUCCUGCCAAACUGCAGUCUUGUAUUGCCGGAGGACAGGAAGGCUCUGCCAGCAUUGGGCUUCCCUGACAGGAUCCGUCGACAGCCUGCUUACAUGACAUCUCCACUCCCUUGGGAAGUUUUGGGCUUGGUAACCUCUUGCCCCUGACUGGGCAUGGCCUGCUGAGCUGUUCUCCUACAGUUCCCGUUGGUCUUCUAUUUCCAGUCAACUGGAGUCAACUUCUUCUCUUUAUCUAAUAUAAAUCAGAACCUAGUUUACUAAGUAAACAAACCAGUAAACAUUCAGCCAGCAAUUUUUAUUUUAUUUUGAGACAGAGUUUCCCUCUUGUUGCCCAGGCUGGAGUUCAAUGGCGCAAUCCCGGCUCACUGCAACCUUCGCCUCCCAGGUUCAAGUGAUUCUCCUGCCUCAGCCUCCCAAGUAGCUGGGAUUACAGGUGCCUGCCACCACACCCAGCUAAUUUUUGUAUUUUUAGUAGAGACAGGGUUUCACCACAUUGGCCAGGCUGGUCUCGAACUCCUGACCUCAGGUGAUCCAUCCGCCUCGGCCUCCCAAAGUGCUGGGAUUACAGGUGUGAGCCACCAUGCCCAGCAUUUUUUUAAAAUUAUUAUUAUUAUUUUAUUUUAUUUUUUUAGAUGGAGUCUCACUCUGUUGCCCAGGCUGGAGUGUGCAUUGGUGCAAUCUCAGCUCACUGCAACCUCCACCUCCCAGGUUCAAGCGAUACUCCUGCCUCGGCUUUGCAAGUAGCCAGGACUACAGGCAUGUGCCACCACGCCCAGCUAAUUUUUGUCUUUUUAGUACAGAUGGGGUUUUGUUAUGUUGGCCAGGCUGGUCUCGGGCUCCUGACCUCAGGUGAUCCACCUGCCUUGGCCGCCUCCCAAAGUGCUGGGAUUACAGGCAGGAGCCACCACACCCAGCCUCAAUUAUUUUUUUAAUGCCUCCUGUGUGCCAGUCACUGUCCUGAUGUCAUUUUGGACAUUCAAAGCUGUGUUAGAUUGGACCCCUCCCUGUCUUCAGAUUUUAUAGUCCAAUUGAGGCAACUAGAAAUAACACACAUUACAAGGUAGAUGACAGAAGACAUAGUCACAAUUCAACUAGCACAUACUUACUUGACUGAGUAACUGUUUUAUGUGAGGUAAUAGGAGCCAAGUGUCUCCUUGAUGCAGCCGAAGAUCUCUAGGUCGAGGAACCGGUGCCAUGAGGUUGUCCUCCACUCUUCCUGACCACUGCCAUGGUGGCAAACCUCAGGGUCUGCUACUUAUCUCCUCCCUCAUUCUGAGGAAUGUCAUAGGAAGGUGUCUGUCACCUCUGGCUCAGUGGGUAGGGAAGGAUAAAUGUUCUUUGAAGUGAGAAAGAACUUCAGUCUGUCCGGUUGUCAAUUUGGAGCAAGUAAGUUUUGGCCUUAUUGUUUGUUUCUUCCAGAGAGCUCUCUCUGAGGAUGUGUGACAUUGGAGUUAUUCAUUCAUUGGUCACCAAAUGCUUGGGAGGUCAGAUGGUGGCUCCCAGAUUGAAUUCAGAAAUAGACCUAAGUCAACACUUUAGCAGCAAGUUGGUUCAAGGGGAAGCAAGCCGCUAUUGGUCACUUGACUCCUUGCCAUCCCUUGUGGCUUGAAUGCAGGCUGGAAAGGUGAGGUGUGUCCGGAGCCAGAACUCUGGAGGCUCUCAGUCUUCUUCCUGAAUUUUAGGGUUCCCCACAGAGACCAUUUCCAAGCUAUACGGGAAGAAAGAGGAAACCCCAGGGUUCUUUGGCAACAAGCUUGCUUUUUUUCUGGUUCUUGGUAUGCUCCACCAGCAGCAGCAUCACCUGGGAGCUUGUUAGAAACUGAAUUCUCAGCUGGGCAACAUAGUGGGAUCCCGUCUCUACAAAAAAGUUUAAAAAUUAGCCAGGCAUGGUGGCACGCGACUGUGGUCCCAGCUACUUGGGAGGCUGAGGCAGAAGGAUCGCUUGAGCCCAGGAGAUAGAGGCUGCAGUGAGCAGUGAUCAUGCACUCCAGCUUGAGUGACAGAGUAAGACUGUCUCAAAAGCAAACAAACAAAAAGAAAUCUAAAUUCUCAGGCCCCACUCCAAACCUACUGAAUCUCUGGGAUCCAGCUAUCUGUGUCUGAACAAGCCUUGCAGGUGACUCUGGUGGACAUGAAGGAUUGAGAGCCACUGAUCCAAUCAUUUUGAAUUAAACUGAGGCCCAGGAGCAUUAAGGAAUGACAUCUUGGUUACAUUUCACCAAGUCUUCGUGCUGUGAUUUUUCUCUCCUUGCUAGAGCUUUAUAUUUUUACCUUACUUCUAAGGCCACGAGAUCAUUUCUUGCCCUCAUUAUUAGUUUUUCCUAAAAUUAAUGAUUGGACUUAACCUUCCAGAGAUAAUACUUUUCAUAUCACAGCUCUUUUUAUGGCAUCUUGUUUUCUGCUUUGGUCUGACCUAUGUUCUUCAUCUUCUACCUCCGAUUUCAUCCUUAAAGCUUUCCCAUGAAUUUCUUAAAGGGGAGAGGGGAAGGGCCCUAAUAUAUUUUAUUCUUCAGUUCAGAAGUGGUUCAGGAAAUUAUAUUUUAAGUGCAAGGUGCCCCUAGCAUCUUUGCCACAGUUGAAUGUUUUCUUAAGUCUGUCACUAAAAGGUGGGCUUCUGUGCCCAAUUCUUGGCACUUCUGUGGUUCAUUAGAAAAACACUAAGUUUGCAGGCCAGGCUUGGUGGCUCAUGCAUGUAAUCCCAGCACUUUGGGAGGCCGAGGCGGGCGGAUCACAAGGUCAGGAGUUUGAGACCAGCCUGACCAACCUGGUGAAACCUCGUCUAUACUAAAAACACAAAAAUUAGCUGGGCGUGUUGGCACGUGCCUAUAGUCCCAGCUACUCAGGAGGCUGAGGCAGGAGAAUUGCUUGAACCCAGGAGAUGGAGGUUGCAGUGAGCCGAGAUCACGCCACUGCACUCCAGUCUGGGUGACAGAGCGAGACUCCAUCUCAAAAAAAAAAGAAAAGAAAAGUAAAAAGAAAACAUUUUUGUAGAGACAGGAUCUUGCUGUGUUGUUCAAGCUGGUUUCGAACUCCUAACCUCAGGCAAUCAUCCUACUUUGGCCCCCCAAAGUGCUGGAAUUAUAGGUGGGAGCCACUGUGCCCAGCAGAUUUCAGCUUCUCCAAUCUCUCCCUUGACUUCCUGGCAGGAGAGCUAGAUAAACUCAGGUAGACAUGUCUUUCAUGGCUACCCAAAGACUCUGUACAGCUAGCCCUCAGGAGCCUGUUUAAGUCAAGAUGUCCUUGCAGUCCCACACUGAUACUACUGAGCCCUAAGUUUAAGAGUGCUGUUAUUCAGGGUUGGGCUCAGUGCCUCACACCUCUAAUCCAGCACUUUGGGAGGCCAAGGUGGGCAGAUCGCUUGAACUCAGGAGUUAAAUACCAGCCUGAGCAACAUGAUGAAAUCCCAUCUCUACCAAAAAUACAAAAAAUUAGCUGGGCACAGUGGCGUGCACCUGUGGUCCCAGCUACUUGGGAGGCUGAGGUGGGAGGUUAGCUUGAGCCCAGGAAGCGGAGGUUGCAAUGAGCCAAGAUUAUACCACUGGGUAACAAAGCGAGUCCCCAUCUAAAAAAACAAAAACAGACUAUUUUUCAGAUUCAAGAAGAGAGGUCUUUCCCUCUUUCCUCACCUCUUGAGGCAUGAAACAGGAAUUCCUUAUCCUAGUUUUAUCACCACCAAACUCCUAGCAGUCAUAAAAGUCCUUUUUCCUCUAAACCCACCUCCUCUCUGCCUCACACUGCAGUAUCCACUCUGUCGCCAGCAGCGAGGCAUUAUAGCAGGAGGCUUCUGAAUUGGCCAGAACAGCAGCUCUCAGGUGGGGUGUCUGAGAACCUCAUUUCCUCAUUACAUCCCUCCCUGGUCAGCCAUAUGUGUUCAGCAGCCAAAUGGCAAAAUUCACCCCCAGAACUGUGAUUGUCUUCCCUAAUCUGGAAGGCCCACAAGUGUGGAGAAGCACUGGAGACCCUCCAGAAGCAGUAGUGCUAGCAGUCAGGGGCUACUCUCCCUGCCGGGCCCCGUGCAAGGGCCUGGCCACCCUAUCCCAGGUAUGUGACACUUGGCUGGCUGUUCUUUAUUGUCCUGCUAGUACCUGUUGUAAAGCUUCUUUUAUUAAAGAAGAGCAGGAGAUUGAAGUGUCAUAAAUUGAAGAGAUUCACACCAACACGGCACAUGUAUACAUAUGUAACAAACCUGCACGUUGUGCACAUGUACCCUAGAACUUAAAGUAUAAUAACAAAAUAUGUAUUAAAAAAAUAAAUAAAUAAAUUGAAGAGAUUGAAUGAUGUCAUAGACUACCAAUCCACAUGCCUUGUUCCUUGCUGCAGCACUGAGGUUUGUAAUCCUGGGAGUUUAGACCUACGUAAGAUGCCCAUAAGUACAAAUGACAGAUGCUCUGUGGGGUUCUUCAGGGUCAAGGUGGCAGAGGUGGGGGUAGGAAGUGAGAGGAGGGGGAAGGGUUGACCAGAGGCACCAAUUUGUCUCCUGUGGGCUUGGUCAGUAUGUGAGCUACCAGGGGGCCAGGCUGGGCCUGACUCUCGGAGAGGCCUAAUAAACAGUACGUAUGAUAAAACAA